GAGCGCAGAGCGGUUUGGUCGUUCGUUGGGCGGUGCUGGUUUUUCGCUCGUCGACUGCGGCUCUUCCUCGGGCAGCGGAAGCGGCGCGGCGGUCGGAGAAGUGGCCUAAAACUUCGGCGUUGGGUGAAAGAAAAUGGCCCGAACCAAGCAGACUGCUCGUAAGUCCACCGGUGGGAAAGCCCCCCGCAAACAGCUGGCCACGAAAGCCGCCAGGAAAAGCGCUCCCUCUACCGGCGGGGUGAAGAAGCCUCAUCGCUACAGGCCCGGGACCGUGGCGCUUCGAGAGAUUCGUCGUUAUCAGAAGUCGACCGAGCUGCUCAUCCGGAAGCUGCCCUUCCAGAGGUUGGUGAGGGAGAUCGCGCAGGAUUUCAAAACCGACCUGAGGUUUCAGAGCGCAGCCAUCGGUGCGCUGCAGGAGGCUAGCGAAGCGUACCUGGUGGGUCUGUUCGAAGAUACCAACCUGUGUGCCAUCCACGCUAAGAGAGUCACCAUCAUGCCCAAAGACAUCCAGUUGGCUCGCCGGAUACGGGGAGAGAGAGCUUAAGUGAAGGCAGUUUUUAUGGCGUUUUGUAGUAAAUUCUGUAAAAUACUUUGGUUUAAUUUGUGACUUUUUUUGUAAGAAAUUGUUUAUAAUAUGUUGCAUUUGUACUUAAGUCAUUCCAUCUUUCACUCAGGAUGAAUGCGAAAAGUGACUGUUCACAGACCUCAGUGAUGUGAGCACUGUUGCUCAGGAGUGACAAGUUGCUAAUAUGCAGAAGGGAUGGGUGAUACUUCUUGCUUCUCAUGAUGCAUGUUUCUGUAUGUUAAUGACUUGUUGGGUAGCUAUUAAGGUACUAGAGUUGAUAAAUGUGUACAGGGUCCUUUUGCAAUAAAACUGGUUAUGACUUGAUCCAAGUGUUUAACAAUUGGGGCUGUUAAGUCUGACCAUACAUCACUGUGAUAGAAUGUGGGCUUUUUCAAGGGUGAAGAUACAAGUCUUAACCACAGUGUAACUUACAGUUUCCUUUAAAAAAAAAAAAAGUAAACCUGGCAGCUAUAGAAUACACUAUGUGCAUUUAUAAUAGCUAUUUUAUAUAUUGUAGUAUCAACAUUUUUAAAUUAAAUGUUUUACAUUCACAAGUGGUGGGGAGUCUUGUCAUUAAGGUGUGUGUAAUUUAGAGUCCAGUUGGUUUUCUUCUGACUGCACUUGUUCUCAUAGUAGUAAAAUGCUAUGCGCAUUUAUACCUUGCAUAAGUCCUCAUUCUACCACAUGUUAACCCUCUAGCUGAUAAUGCAAACACUAACUGGGGGAUUUUAUUUAUAAGGGCUCUAGAAAAAACGAGUUAUUCACACCAGCAUCAUCUUAACUAACAUUCUGAACUAGUUAGUGCAGCUUUUCAUUGUGUUGUGUGGUUGGUCUCAUAACUAGGUUGAGUUUUUCUCCUCUGCUGAGGAAACAGUACCGAAGUUCUUUUUCUUGUGGCAUUUGUAUUAUAAAAACUUGGUGUGGGGGAGGAGCACAAAACUCCAGCCCACUGAACCUCUGCCAAUUAAGAUGGUGUUGGGUUAGGUUACAUCUGGUUACUGUCCUGGGAAAAUCAUUUUUAUAGAGAUGGCCUUCCAAGUGGUUUUAAAAUUUACUGAAGUUUUUAGGUCAAUUAUGUAUGUUGACUAAAUUUACAAAUAAACUUGUUUAUCCAACUAAGUGUCCAAAACCUAAAUUGAAUGUACUAAGUUUUCACAUGUCCCAUUAUCUAGGUCCUUGUAUACUAAUGUUUUGAACUUAGAUCAUUUCAGGUGUUGUUUGGUGGAUAAAGGAACCUUUUAUUUAUAAAGAUACUGUAGAAAGCAUGUGAACAGCUCUCUGCUUGAUUAAGAUGCCAUAAUAGUGCUGUAUUUGCAGUGUGGGCUAAGACAAAGUAUAUUAAUAAGCUUUUCAGCCCCCCCACUCCCGUUCCGUAGUGUAGAAGCCCACAGGUGUAGAACUCAGUCUUAAACUUCAGUAUGAAACCAGUUUCCUUGUGCGAUGAUGGCCACUAAAGCAUAGUACGUGGAUGUCAGUGAGACAGCAUGAGAGCCAGCAGUCAUCAAAGCGUUCCACGUUUGAAGUUAGCAACUGCUUAAAGUUAUACCCCAUUAAAAUUGCUUUCUCAAAAGUUUGGGUUAGUUUCAAAUGUGAUAUUUUGGAGGGAAGGUAAAGUAGGUAUCUUUCAGGUCGUGAUAAUGAGCUCCUAUGAAAGGAUGCAAUAUAAUGACCCGCUUUUCUAGAAAGUUCAUAAUCAGCUCUGGAACAAGCACACUUGAUUCCUCACUGUGCUUCAGAAUGAGAUUAAGAUCAGAUGUUGGAACGUGCUAUGCUGUAGCGUGUCUGGAAACAAAGUACACAAACCUGGCUACGGUGAUGAGUUAGCUUCUGCUUACUACCUGUGACAACCCAAGUGGGUGACACUAGUGAACCUUCUCCAGUCUGCAGGCUGGCAUAGAAGGCUCUUAGAUUAUAUUGGGCAGCUUGCAAUCUGCCGAAGCAGUGACUUGCAUUUCCACACUUGGCUUGAGCACUCAACCCAGAAGGCGAAGAUAGCUUUUGGUUGUAGGCGGCUUCCUGUAUGGGAUAUCCCUCGGUAAGGGUAAAGGAGCAGAGGCAAAGGAGAAAAGCAGAAGUUGCAGCUGAUGCAGGUAUCCUAUGCCCUUGAUGGAUGAGACUAAAAUAAAAUUUUUGAAGUUAA